AAACGAGUUUCAAUCCACUUUCCUGACCCCAACCAUCCUGCCCAGUCUCCGCUUCCCCGUCUUGUACACCCCUAACUCCUGAGGCUCCUCCGAAUCACGCGAGUGGAAGCGGAGAAGCUCAAGUGGCCGCCAUGUCAGAGGCUUAUUUCCGAGUGGAGUCGGGUGCGCUGGGGCCUGAGGAGAACUUUCUUUCUUUGGACGACAUCCUGAUGUCCCACGAGAAGCUGCCGGUGCGCACGGAGACCGCCAUGCCUCGCCUUGGCGCUUUCUUCCUGGAGCGGAGCGCAGGCGCCGAGACUGACAACGCGGUCCCACAGGGUUUUGCUCUGUUGCCCAGGCUGGAGUGCAGUGGUGUGAUAUGGCUCACUGCAGCCUUGACCUCCCAGGCUCCAGAGAUCCUCCCACCUCAGCCACCUAUGUGGCUGGUAUUGCAGGGUUCCAAGCUUGAACUACCCUUGUGGCUGGCAAAAGGACUUUUUGACAACAAGCGACGGAUCCUUUCUGUGGAACUCCCCAAGAUCUACCAAGAGGGUUGGAGGACUGUGUUCAGUGCAGAUCCCAAUGUGGUGGACCUCCACAAAAUGGGGCCCCAUUUCUACGGGUUUGGCUCCCAGCUCCUGCAUUUUGACAGUCCCGAGAAUGCAGACAUUUCCCAGUCUCUGCUGCAGACUUUUAUCGGACGUUUUCGCCGCAUCAUGGACUCCUCACAGAAUGCUUACAACGAAGACACUUCAGCCCUGGUAGCCAGGCUAGACGAGAUGGAGAGGGGCUUAUUUCAAACAGGGCAGAAAGGACUGAAUGACUUUCAGUGUUGGGAGAAGGGGCAGGCUUCUCAGAUCACAGCUUCCAACCUCGUUCAGAAUUACAAGAAGAGAAAAUUCACUGAUAUGGAAGACUGAAAGCCGGAAGAACACAGAAUGGCUCCUCACAGACGUAUCCCUCCGUGUGUCCUUGAUAGGAGCUGGUUGACCUUGUACAGAACCAGAAUCCUGUCCCAUUUCAUGGCUUAUUUCCUGUGGCCAUAGAGAAUUAUAGGGAACUGGACAUGCUGGAGGAUGUGGGUGUCCCUGGCUCUGUGAGUCUUCCAGGACCGUCCCACCCUGCUGACCCACAGCCCAGGCCCUUUAACCCAAGAACCCAUGGCCAAGGAGAAAUCAAAGUCCUUCCUAAAUAAGAAUCACUGCCAUAUAAUAUAUCACAGUAGAGUUGCAACUGAGAUUCCUUGUGUCUGGGAGUUUGGACAGCUUCAGAUGUACAGUUUCACUAGCCACAAAGCACAGGUACAAACUGGGUCAUCGCCUGUUCACAAAAUGCUCUCUUGAUCUUAUUUGCCUCAUCUUCCUCAUGGUUGUACAGAGGAUAGCACCCCACCAUGCCAGCCUGACUUGGAGAUAUCUCCUGCUGCCUGCCUGCAGGGAGUUACCCCAGUUUCCAAAAACAGUCGCCCAGAUAAAGGAGGAAAAGGGAAAGGCAGACGAAUGGCAUGGCUUUUACUAAAGAAAAGAUGUUGGCCUCAUACUCUAUACUCAGGGCUUAAUGAACUGGAAUCUGCAUAACUCAGCAGUCAACCCAGAAGGGAAAUGGUUAAACUGAGCUUGUUAUUGCCUCGGAGAGCCUAAGAGCACCCGCACACUUAAUUCUACUCCCUGUCUAGAAAAGCUGUCAGGGAGUCGUUUGGAAUUGCAAUGUAGUUAUUAAGGGCUGUUAACCAGCCUGCAUUACAUCUGGAAGUCAGGACUUGGGUGCUGACUAUGAAGGGCCCUGUUUUCAAAAUCUAACAUUGCAAGUGUAAAUGGGCAAGAAGCCUCCGUUGUGCUUUUUUUUUCCUCUUCAGUAACUUUUGCAACAUUAUUGCAUAGAAGAUCCCUGACCAUUUACUAGGAACCUGGUUAAGCAAGCACUAAUCUCUUUUCCUGGAGAUCAAGGAUGCAACCUCAGGUUGAGAAAGAAACAGGGUUCCCUGGGCCCAUUAGACUGUUUGCAGGGCAUCACUGCUUCCCCCUGACACCUCACAACUAGCAAAAAUUGUCUUUGUCUUUGGAAAUUAUAGAGGGAUUUGGGUAUCCAGAUUGUGCAGAUGCAAACUUAGGCUGUCUUGAUGCAAACUUAGAACCACAGAAAUGCUUUUAAAAUGCCUGUUUUAAGAUGGAAUUGUUGUUUUUAUAAUUUGAUUUUAGUGCUAAAUAAAUGAUUGGCUUUGUACAUGAAUAUGUUCUGUACAAGUGCUCUUUCACUAGUACUACAGAUAAUCAAAGCUAUCAGAAUUGUGUCUUUGAUCAUAUUUGACGGUAAUACACAAAUCCAUGUUUUAGCAGCU